GCAUUUCUCCUCUGUGCUCACUGCCACACACAGCUCAACCUGGACAGCACAGCCAGAGGCGAGAUGCUUCUCUGCUGAUCUGAGUCUGCCUGCAGCAUGGACCUGGGUCUUCCCUGAAGCAUCUCCAGGGCUGGAGGGACGACUGCCAUGCACCGAGGGCUCAUCCAUCCGCAGAGCAGGGCAGUGGGAGGAGACGCCAUGACCCCCAUCGUCACAGUCCUGAUCUGUCUCGGGCUGAGUCUGGGCCCCAGGACCCGCGUGCAGACAGGGACCAUCCCCAAGCCCACCCUGUGGGCUGAGCCAGACUCUGUGAUCACCCAGGGGAGUCCCGUCACCCUCAGUUGUCAGGGGAGCCUUGAAGCCCAGGAGUACCGUCUAUAUAGGGAGAAAAAAUCAGCAUCUUGGAUUACACGGAUACGACCAGAGCUUGUGAAGAACGGCCAGUUCCACAUCCCAUCCAUCACCUGGGAACACACAGGGCGAUAUGGCUGUCAGUAUUACAGCCGCGCUCGGUGGUCUGAGCUCAGUGACCCCCUGGUGCUGGUGAUGACAGGAGCCUACCCAAAACCCACCCUCUCAGCCCAGCCCAGCCCUGUGGUGACCUCAGGAGGAAGGGUGACCCUCCAGUGUGAGUCACAGGUGGCAUUUGGCGGCUUCAUUCUGUGUAAGGAAGGAGAAGAUGAACACCCACAAUGCCUGAACUCCCAGCCCCAUGCCCGUGGGUCGUCCCGCGCCAUCUUCUCCGUGGGCCCCGUGAGCCCGAAUCGCAGGUGGUCGCACAGGUGCUAUGGUUAUGACUUGAACUCUCCCUAUGUGUGGUCUUCACCCAGUGAUCUCCUGGAGCUCCUGGUCCCAGGUGUUUCUAAGAAGCCAUCACUCUCAGUGCAGCCGGGUCCUGUCAUGGCCCCUGGGGAAAGCCUGACCCUCCAGUGUGUCUCUGAUGUCGGCUAUGACAGAUUUGUUCUGUACAAGGAGGGGGAACGUGACCUUCGCCAGCUCCCUGGCCGGCAGCCCCAGGCUGGGCUCUCCCAGGCCAACUUCACCCUGGGCCCUGUGAGCCGCUCCUACGGGGGCCAGUACAGAUGCUACGGUGCACACAACCUCUCCUCUGAGUGCUCGGCCCCCAGCGACCCCCUGGACAUCCUGAUCACAGGACAGAUCCGUGGCACACCCUUCAUCUCAGUGCAGCCAGGCCCCACAGUGGCCUCAGGAGAGAACGUGACCCUGCUGUGUCAGUCAUGGCGGCAGUUCCACACUUUCCUUCUGACCAAGGCGGGAGCAGCUGAUGCCCCACUCCGUCUAAGAUCAAUACACGAAUAUCCUAAGUACCAGGCUGAAUUCCCCAUGAGUCCUGUGACCUCAGCCCACGCGGGGACCUACAGGUGCUACGGCUCACUCAACUCCGACCCCUACCUGCUGUCUCACCCCAGUGAGCCCCUGGAGCUCGUGGUCUCAGGACCCUCCAUGGGUUCCAGCCCCCCACCCACCGGUCCCAUCUCCACACCUGCAGGCCCUGAGGACCAGCCCCUCACCCCCACUGGGUCGGAUCCCCAAAGUGGUCUGGGAAGGCACCUGGGGGUUGUGAUCGGCAUCUUGGUGGCCGUCGUCCUACUGCUCCUCCUCCUCCUCCUCCUCUUCCUCAUCCUCCGACAUCGACGUCAGGGCAAACACUGGACAUCGACCCAGAGAAAGGCUGAUUUCCAACAUCCUGCAGGGGCUGUGGGGCCAGAGCCCACAGACAGAGGCCUGCAGUGGAGGUCCAGCCCAGCUGCCGACGCCCAGGAAGAAAACCUCUAUGCUGCCGUGAAGGACACACAGCCUGAAGAUGGGGUGGAGAUGGACACUCGGGCUGCUGCAUCUGAAGCCCCCCAGGAUGUGACCUACGCCCAGCUGCACAGCUUGACCCUCAGACGGAAGGCAACUGAGCCUCCUCCAUCCCAGGAAAGGGAACCUCCAGCUGAGCCCAGCAUCUACGCCACCCUGGCCAUCCACUAGCCCGGAGGGUACGCAGACUCCACACUCAGUAGAAGGAGACUCAGGACUGCUGAAGGCACGGGAGCUGCCCCCAGUGGACACCAAUGAACCCCAGUCAGCCUGGACCCCUAACAAAGACCAUGAGGAGAUGCUGGGAACUUUGGGACUCACUUGAUUCUGCAGUCGAAAUAACUAAUAUCCCUACAUUUUUUAAUUAAAGCAACAGACUUCUCAAUAAUCAAUGAGUUAACCGAGAAAACUAAAAUCAGAAGUAAGAAUGUGCUUUAAACUGAAUCACAAUAUAAAUAUUACACAUCACACAAUGAAAUUGAAAAAGUACAAACCACAAAUGAAAAAAGUAGAAACGAAAAAAAAAAACUAGGAAAUGAAUGACGUUGGCUUUCGUAUAAGGAAUUUAGAAAAAGAAUAACCAAUUAUUCCAAAUGAAGGUGUAAGAAAGGGAAUAAGAAGAAGAAGAGUUGCUCAUGAGGAAAAACCAAAACUUGAAAAUUCAACAAAGCCAAUGAAGCUCAUUCUUGAAAAUAUUAAUUACAGUCAUAAAUCCUAACUACAUUGAGCAAGAGAAAGAAAGAGCAGGCACGCAUUUCCAUAUGGGAGUGAGCCAGCAGACAGCCCAGCAGAUCCUACACACAUUUUCACAAACUAACCCCAGAACAGGCUGCAAACCUAUACCAAUAUACUAGAAAAUGCAGAUUAAAUGGAUGAAAUAUUCAAAACUGGAGUUUACAUAAUGAACGUAAGAGUAAUCAGAGAAUCUGACUCAUUUUAAAUGUGUGUGUAUGUGUGUGUAUAUAUAUGUGUGUGUGUGUGUGUGUGUGUGUGUGUGAAAAACAUUGACUGUAAUAAAAAUGUUCCCAUCGUAUCAACUCCA